ACCCUGGCCCUGCACGCAGAGCUCCCAUCCAGGCGCGCGCGGCGGCAGCAGCAGCUGUCGCGGAGAGGCCGGGGCCGGCGCGCCUGGUGCGGGCCCGGGGGUGGCGGGUCGGGCGCCCAGGUCCCGGGGGUCGCGCUGAGCCACAGCCGGGUGCCCGACCCCGGCCCGCCGUGCUCACCAGCUGGGAUAGGGAGACCCGGCGGGCGCAGCCCGGCCGCCACCGUCCGUGAAUUAUGCAGGAAGCUGGCACCGGCGCGCUCGAGUUGAUCAAGUUUCCCUGGCAACUUUCGCCCGGGCAUCCCUCCUCCCCGGCGGCCGGGCAGCUCCGCCCGCCCAGCCCGCGGCCCAGGCGCCUCCACCGGGUGGCCCCGGCCCCGGGCGCCAGGCGCGGGGACCGCUCCCAGAGACGCCGACAGCGCACUCGUCACUUGGGCUGGAGCCGCCGGACUGAGCCAGCAGGUCUGGAAAUCUCUCCAGGCACCCUGCUUUGGCCCUCUAGAAUACAGACAGUUCCUGCUCUAAGAGGCCAUCUGUGAGGCUCAGUCUCCCAACACCUCUGACACAGGCAGCCAUGCCGCGCAGCCCAACAUCCAGCGAGGACGAGAUGGCCCAGAGCUUCUCCGACUACUCCGUGGGGUCGGAGUCAGACAGCUCCAAAGAAGAGACCAUCUAUGACACGAUCCGGGCCACUGCGGAGAAGCCGGGCGGUGCCAGGACGGAGGAGAGCCAGGGCAACACGCUGGUGAUCCGCGUGGUCAUCCAUGACCUGCAGCAGACGAAAUGCAUUCGAUUUAACCCGGAUGCCACAGUGUGGGUUGCAAAGCAGCGGAUCCUGUGUACAUUAACCCAGAGUUUGAAAGAUGUCCUGAACUACGGCCUGUUCCAGCCGGCCAGCAAUGGGCGUGACGGCAAGUUCCUGGAUGAGGAGCGGCUCCUGCGCGAGUACCCACAGCCCGUGGGUGAGGGCGUUCCUUCCCUGGAGUUUCGAUACAAGAAGCGGGUGUAUAAACAAGCCAGUCUCGAUGAGAAACAGUUGGCCAAGCUCCACACGAAGACCAAUCUGAAGAAAUGCAUGGAUCACAUUCAGCAUCGCUUGGUGGAGAAGAUCACCAAGAUGCUGGACCGAGGCCUGGAUCCCAAUUUCCACGACCCGGAGACCGGAGAGACCCCCCUGACCUUAGCCGCUCAGCUGGACGACUCUGUGGAGGUCAUCAAAGCUCUCAAAAAUGGUGGAGCUCACCUGGACUUCCGUGCCAAAGAUGGGAUGACCGCCCUACACAAAGCUGCCCGAGCGAGGAACCAAGUUGCCCUGAAGACCCUUUUAGAGCUUGGUGCAUCCCCAGAUUAUAAAGACAGUUACGGCCUCACCCCGCUGUAUCACACAGCCAUCGUCGGAGGUGAUCCCUACUGCUGCGAGCUUCUCCUGCACGAACACGCCACUGUGUGCUGCAAAGAUGAGAACGGCUGGCACGAGAUCCACCAGGCCUGCAGGUACGGGCACGUGCAGCACCUGGAGCACCUGCUGUUCUACGGGGCAGACAUGAGUGCCCAGAAUGCCUCGGGGAACACGGCCUUGCACAUCUGCGCCCUCUACAACCAGGACAGCUGUGCAAGAGUGCUUCUGUUUCGAGGCGGAAAUAAGGAGUUAAAAAACUACAACAGCCAGACUCCAUUUCAGGUGGCCAUAAUAGCAGGCAACUUUGAGCUGGCAGAAUACAUCAAGAACCACAAGGAAACAGACAUUGUGCCCUUCCGAGAGGCCCCGGCGUACUCCAACCGCCGGCGGCGGCCCCCCAACACGCUGGCCGCCCCCCGGGUCCUGCUGCGCUCCAACAGUGACAACAACCUCAAUGCCAGCGCUCCCGACUGGGCCGUCUGCUCCACGGCCACCUCGCACCGCAGCCUGUCACCCCAGCUGCUGCAGCAGAUGCCCAGCAAGCCCGAGGGGGCCGCGAAGACCAUUGGGAGCUACGUGCCCGGGCCCCGCAGCCGGUCCCCAUCGCUCAACAGGCUGGGCGGCGCAGGCGAGGACGGCAAGAGGCCGCAGCCUCUCUGGCAUGUCGGGUCGCCUUUUGCUCUUGGUGCCAACAAGGACUCACUCUCGGCCUUCGAGUACCCGGGGCCCAAGCGGAAGCUCUACAGUGCCGUGCCCGGGAGGCUCUUCGUCGCUGUCAAGCCAUACCAACCCCAAGUGGACGGCGAGAUCCCCCUUCACCGCGGUGACAGGGUCAAAGUUCUGAGCAUCGGUGAAGGGGGCUUCUGGGAAGGCAGCGCCCGCGGCCACAUCGGAUGGUUUCCGGCGGAGUGCGUGGAGGAGGUCCAGUGUAAGCCCAGGGACAGCCAGGCAGAAACCCGCGCUGACCGCAGCAAGAAGCUUUUCAGGCACUACACCGUGGGCUCCUAUGACAGCUUCGACACUUCCAGUGACUGCAUUAUUGAGGAGAAGACGGUGGUCCUGCAGAAAAAAGACAAUGAGGGCUUUGGAUUCGUGCUUCGAGGGGCCAAAGCUGACACACCCAUUGAAGAAUUCACACCAACACCGGCUUUCCCAGCCCUACAGUACCUGGAGUCCGUGGAUGAAGGUGGGGUGGCGUGGCAAGCCGGACUAAGGACCGGGGACUUCUUGAUUGAGGUUAACAAUGAGAAUGUUGUCAAAGUCGGCCACAGGCAGGUGGUGAACAUGAUCCGGCAGGGAGGGAAUCACCUGGUCCUUAAGGUGGUCACGGUGACCAGGAAUCUGGACCCCGACGACACCGCCAGGAAGAAAGCUCCCCCGCCUCCAAAGCGGGCACCGACCACAGCCCUCACCCUGCGCUCCAAGUCCAUGACCUCGGAGCUGGAGGAGCUCGUGGAUAAAGCCUCGGUCCGGAAGAAGAAGGAUAAACCCGAGGAGAUAGUCCCGGCCUCCAAGCCCUCCCGCGCUGCUGAGAACAUGGCUGUGGAACCGAGGGUGGCGACCAUCAAGCAGCGGCCCAGCAGCCGGUGCUUCCCGGCGGGCUCAGACAUGAACUCUGUGUACGAACGCCAAGGAAUCGCCGUGAUGACGCCCACUGUUCCUGGGAGCCCAAAAGCCCCGUUUCUGGGCAUCCCUCGAGGUACGAUGCGAAGGCAGAAAUCAAUAGACAGCAGAAUCUUUCUAUCAGGAAUAACAGAGGAAGAGCGGCAGUUUCUGGCUCCUCCAAUGCUGAAGUUCACCAGAAGCCUGUCCAUGCCGGACACCUCUGAGGACAUCCCCCCUCCACCGCAGUCUGUGCCCCCGUCCCCACCACCACCUUCCCCAACCACUUACAACUGCCCCAAGUCCCCAACUCCAAGAGUCUACGGGACGAUUAAGCCUGCGUUCAAUCAGAAUUCUGCCGCCAAGGUGUCCCCCGCCACCAGGUCCGACACCGUGGCCACCAUGAUGAGGGAGAAGGGGAUGUACUUCAGGAGAGAGCUGGACCGCUACUCCUUGGACUCUGAAGACCUCUACAGUCGGAAUGCCGGCCCGCAAGCCAACUUCCGCAACAAGAGAGGCCAGAUGCCAGAAAACCCAUACUCAGAGGUGGGGAAGAUCGCCAGCAAAGCCGUCUACGUCCCCGCCAAGCCCGCCAGGCGGAAGGGGAUGCUGGUGAAGCAGUCCAACGUGGAGGACAGCCCCGAGAAGACGUGCUCCAUCCCUAUCCCGACCAUCAUCGUGAAGGAGCCGUCCACCAGCAGCAGCGGCAAGAGCAGCCAGGGCAGCAGCAUGGAGAUCGACCCCCAGGCCCCGGAGCCACCGAGCCAGCUGCGGCCUGACGAAAGCCUGACCGUCAGCAGCCCCUUUGCCGCCGCCAUCGCCGGAGCCGUCCGCGACCGUGAGAAGCGGCUGGAAGCCAGGAGGAACUCCCCGGCCUUCCUCUCCACAGACCUGGGGGAUGAGGAUGUGGGCCUGGGGCCACCCGCCCCCAGGACGCGGCCCUCCAUGUUCCCCGAGGAGGGGGAUUUUGCUGACGAGGACAGCGCUGAGCAGCUGUCAUCCCCCAUGCCGAGUGCCACGCCCAGGGAGCCCGAAAACCAUUUCGUGGGUGGCGCCGAGGCCAGUGCUCCGGGUGAGGCUGGGAGGCCGCUGAAUUCCACGUCCAAAGCCCAGGGGCCCGAGAGCAGCCCAGCAGUGCCCUCCGCGAGCAGCGGCACAGCCGGCCCCGGGAAUUAUGUCCACCCACUCACAGGGCGGCUGCUUGAUCCCAGCUCCCCGCUGGCCCUGGCACUCUCCGCAAGGGACCGAGCCAUGAAGGAGUCUCAACAGGGACCCAAAGGGGAGGCCCCCAAGGCCGACCUCAACAAACCUCUUUACAUUGAUACCAAAAUGCGGCCCAGCCUGGAUGCCGGCUUCCCUACGGUCACCAGGCAGAACACCCGGGGACCCCUGAGGCGGCAGGAGACGGAGAACAAGUACGAGACCGACCUGGGCCGAGACCGGAAAGGCGAUGACAAGAAGAACAUGCUGAUCGACAUCAUGGACACGUCCCAGCAGAAGUCGGCUGGCCUGCUGAUGGUGCACACCGUGGACGCCACUAAGCUGGACAACGCCCUGCAGGAAGAGGACGAGAAGGCAGAGGUGGAGAUGAAGCCAGACAGCUCGCCGUCCGAGGUGCCAGAAGGUGUUUCCGAAACCGAAGGUGCUUUACAGAUCUCCGCUGCCCCCGAGCCCACCACCGUGCCCGGCAGAACCAUCGUCGCGGUGGGCUCCAUGGAAGAGGCGGUGAUUUUGCCAUUCCGCAUCCCUCCUCCCCCUCUGGCAUCCGUGGACUUGGAUGAGGAUUUUAUUUUUACAGAGCCAUUGCCUCCUCCCCUGGAAUUUGCAAAUAGUUUUGAUAUCCCCGAUGACCGGGCAGCUUCUGUCCCGGCUCUCUCAGACUUAGUGAAGCAGAAGAAAAGCGACACCCCUCAGUCCCCUUCGUUGAACUCCAGCCAACCAACCAACUCUGCAGACAGCAAGAAGCCAGCCAGUCUUUCAAACUGUCUGCCUGCCUCAUUCCUGCCACCCCCUGAAAGCUUUGACGCCGUCGCCGACUCUGGGAUCGAGGAGGUGGACAGCCGGAGUAGCAGCGACCACCACCUCGAGACGACCAGCACUAUCUCCACCGUGUCUAGCAUCUCCACCCUGUCUUCCGAAGGUGGAGAGAAUGUGGACACCUGCACAGUCUAUGCAGAUGGGCAAGCAUUUAUGGUUGACAAACCCCCAGUACCUCCUAAGCCAAAAAUGAAGCCCAUCAUUCACAAAAGCAAUGCACUUUAUCAAGACGCGCUCGUGGAAGAAGAUGUAGAUAGCUUUGUUAUCCCCCCGCCCGCUCCCCCGCCCCCGCCGGGCAGUGCCCAGCCUGGGAUGGCCAAGGUUCUCCAGCCAAGGACCUCCAAGUUGUGGGGCGACGUCACAGAGAUCAAAAGCCCGAUUCUCUCAGGCCCAAAGGCAAACGUUAUUAGUGAAUUGAACUCUAUCCUACAGCAAAUGAACCGAGAGAAAUUGGCAAAGCCGGGGGAAGGACUGGAUUCACCAAUGGGAGCCAAGUCCGCCAGCCUCGCUCCAAGAAGCCCGGAGAUCAUGAGCACCAUCUCAGGUACACGGAGCACGACGGUCACCUUCACUGUUCGCCCCGGCACCUCCCAGCCCAUCACCCUGCAGAGCCGGCCCCCCGACUAUGAAAGCAGGACCUCAGGAACAAGACGUGCCCCAAGCCCUGUGGUCUCGCCAACAGAGAUGAACAAAGAGACCCUGCCCGCCCCCCUGUCUGCUGCCACCGCCUCUCCUUCUCCCGCUCUCUCAGAUGUCUUUAGCCUUCCAAGCCAGCCCCCUUCUGGGGAUCUAUUUGGCUUGAACCCAGCGGGACGCAGUAGGUCGCCAUCCCCCUCGAUACUGCAACAGCCAAUCUCAAAUAAGCCUUUUACAACUAAACCUGUCCACCUGUGGACUAAACCAGAUGUGGCCGAUUGGCUGGAAAGUCUAAACUUGGGUGAACAUAAAGAGGCCUUCAUGGACAAUGAGAUCGAUGGCAGUCACUUACCAAACCUGCAGAAGGAGGACCUCAUCGAUCUUGGGGUAACUCGAGUCGGGCACAGAAUGAACAUAGAAAGGGCUUUGAAACAGCUGCUGGACAGAUAAGGACGGCUGCUCUCCACCUCGCAGACUGCUCUUGUUAUAAGUAGAGAUGGGCUCGUGCUGAAACAUCUGAAUGCCAAGCGAAGUCUGUGAGCAUCAACCCCACUCCAUGGGUUUGUCUCCUGGUACCCAAAGAAAUACUGAGUUGUGUCCACAACAUGGCUGGGUCUUCAGACCCCUGGCUCACCAUGUGGGUGUCUUGGGCAGUUUCUAUCACACAUGGGACAAGGGGAGGGAGUUUUUCUAACAUGGAAAAAGAUUCUCAGCCUGCCGCCCAGCAUGCAGGUGGCCUCGCUUUGCCGGGUCCGAGAGGCUCCCCGUCAAUUUUGCACGGGAUCCUAGCUCUUGUAGGCAGACACCAGUGCACUCUAGAUACCUCCUGAGACCUCCGUCCUCUGCUUUCCGGGCAGCUCUCACCACCCCAGGCCCCGGCAUGAGGCCUUUCCUCAGUCCUGUGGCCUCUCAGAGGACACCUGAUGCUCACCUGCCCCUCUUUCUCCUGCACUUGGCUUGCAGUGAGAUGCUCCCAGAUGCAUUUGUCCAGUGCCCCAUCAUGGGCCUGAAAGGCAGAGAAACUUUUUCCUACACAGAUUCUUUUCCCCAUCUCCUCCUGUGGUUUGCAUCCAUGGCUCUUUGGCCAUGAGGUUCCUGGCAGUGCUGGGAGUUUGGAUGGGAUCGUGCCCAGCUUUGCUUAGCUUUCUUUAUUUCUGCAAAUCUGUUAGCAUAAUUCCAAGGUGGCCAAGCAGAUGUCACAUGGAGUUAGUCAAAGCACAAAGUCACGAUUCCACAAUGGAGGGGAGACCUGGCCAAGGGAGCCAGCCAGCGUGCAACUGCCCAAGCUCCAGGUCUCCAGGACAAGAGCAGUUGUCUGCCAUGAGCACCCAUCCAGGAUGGAGAAUAAGGGCUUCUCUGCCUCUCAGAAUUCUUUUUAAUUGAAGAUGUCUUGAGCUCUGCAAAGAUCAGAGCAGGUGAGCAUCCACUUUGACAUGAAGGACAAGAAGACGCAUGGCUCAUGGCGGGCACAUGCGGCUGCCAGUGAGACAGCGUCUCCUCUGGGAGCUGGGCGGGCACAGCAUCCUCAGUUCUGUGCCCAGCCAAGGGUGAGCAUCUCUGCUGAGACAGUCCUUUUGCUCUCGGAGGCCAGGGAAGAUGGUACUUAGAGGCUUUUCCCCUAUCGCUCUGGGUGUCUAGGAAUCCCACCAGCUUGUCUUAACAGUACAACAGCUUCUUUGAGGACCCAGUGGGUAUGGAGUAUAGACAGAACCCAGGGUUGAGAACAGAAGGUGGGCGGCAGGAUCAGAGUGAAAGCAGAGGCGUGAGGAGAGGAAAGCAGGGAGGUCUCCUGGGCUGCCAGGUCAGCCUCUCUGGCAAGGCUUUCUUGAGCCCCGCCCCUUUCUUUCCCCGGAGUCCCUCCACCCCAUAACAAUACCUCGAAUUUCCAAAAGAGGUCACCAGAUGCACAUGGGCCGCAAAACACACAGUCAGGCUUCCAGCACAUUCUCCCCCAUUUGGAGGAUACUCGAAUGUCAGGUUUUUGGUUUUAUUAUUAUUUCAGAACUAGCUCAGCCCAUCUCUAAUUAUAAAACAUGGUUUUGUUUUUUUUUUUUCCUUUUUUUCUUGAUUAGGUCUGGAACAGCUCUAGAAUGAACACAUAAAAUUUAGCAAUUUAAAAUCUUUCUUUACUGCAAGUUUAAAUAGUUGUACAGAUAGUUUAUAAGCACAAUAUUUUAAGAAAAAAAAGUGGCUGGUCUACUAGGCAGCCUUUGUGCCACUUCAGUGCUAGAAAGUUAAAGAAAAAAAAACUUUUGUGAUUUAAUAAUACUAUUUCUGUGGAAUAAUUAUAAAAGUAUGACCUUUUUAAAUCAACCUUAUUUGGAUGCAUCUGAACCAGCAGAGCUGUGUUAUAUUUUCUAUCUUUGCUAGAACUUCGUCAUUGAAGGACAAUUUCUUCAAAGUGGUUACAAUUCAUAAUGCAGCAGUUUCUCCAAAAACAAAAACAAAACACACACCACACACACGCGCUUUUCCAGUCACACACCCCUGAUGUUGGAACCAAGUUUUUGGACCUUCUGUUCCAAAACCUUUUGCAGGUCAAUCUUUGUAUUUGAAAUGAUCCAAUCCAACUUGAAGUCAAUUGAAUAUUAAGGCGCUUUACUUCCGUGUGCUUUCAGUUUUUCCAUCAUGAGAUGAAUGAGCAUUACUCUAGAUAAAUUUCAAGACAGGAUACUACAGGUGGCCUGCUGAGGCUGCCCCAUAUUUUAGAAAAUGUAAAAAUGGUGGUUUGGCCAUUAAUUUGUCUUCCAUUUGAUGAUACCGCAAAAUUCCGUGAGUCCAUUCCUUUGGCAUGGCACUUUCCCUGGGCCUACAGUUGGUAUUACCUCUGUGCUCAGUGCCAGGCAAAACACUAGCUCAAAGGAGAGUCAAGGAAACCGCUGGCAGACGAUAACCAGUCGAAACUCGUGACUUCGGUUUGUUGAACUUUGGCAGCCAGUUGGUGAGGGCCAGAUGUUAUUCCCUUUCUUAAAGAUACUCCAAGCCACAUGCCACUAACCACAAGCAAGCUGGCUGCAAGACUAAAGAGCUGAUAACAUAGUUUAUUUUUACACUGUCUUAUUAUAGAGAAGUAAUAGACCUAUCAGAACCUGCACUGACCAACAAAUAAACACAUGUUGCCAAGAUGAAUCGGUCUCUAUCUCUAUCUGCUUAUUUUGGUACUGAAAGCAAUAGUUCCUCAUUCAAAUCACCACCCACUGUUCUCCCCCUUUGGGACAUGUUAGGACGAGGCCCUAUUCCAUGCCCCUCUUUAAUGGUGGAACAAAUGUUAAACUGCUCAUCUAAAGAUCAUGUUGAUAUUAUUCCAGGUUUUAAGAUCAACUUUUGUUACAUACUGUAAUUUAAAUAAACUGCAUUUACAUGCCUAGUUUCUGUAAUAUUGUGUAUACAAAACCCAAAUCUCUCAAAAUGUAAAUUAUGUAUACCUGCCAAGAUACCUUUUCCAGGGUGUCUGCGCACAUUUUAAGUUAAUUCACAUAAUAUAAAAAUUACUCAAUGUGACUGUUGAUUUGCUGAACUUUACAUAUCACAAAGUGAAUUAUUUGUGAUACUUUAGUUAAUAAAAUGGUAAAUUUUUUUCUCAGUUAUUGAACAAGCAAGCAUUAUCCAGUUGAUCUGGCAAUGACUUUUUGUGUGUGGGCCACAAUAUUGAUUUUCCCAUUAACAAUUUUUUUUUGUUUUUUAAAUACUAAUAUGUUUCACACUAUAGUUUGUGUAACAACACGUGUUCGCAUUAUCUAUGUUGCUGUUACUUUUGUGCUUUUAUUCUUUUUAGACUUUAUAAAAAAAAAAAAAAGCUCCUGUAAUUUGCACUUUCUCCCAAUCCUUAAAUCUCUUGUAUGGCAACCAAAAUUACUGUAAAAAAAUAAAUAUACUAUUGCACUAAGGUUGUGGUUCUGAUUGCAAACAAACAGUGAACACUGUCUGAAUUAAACAAAAAGCUGCCCGACUUGCAAUCUAAUGUAGAUUAUCUCAGGCAUUGUGGCCAGCUCUGCCUCUCUAAAACUGACCAGAAAAAUCUCUCUCAUCGAGUAAACAGGCUCCUGUCACUGAGCUAAUCUGCCUUGGUUCCAUUUCCUUAUUCUCAAUUUAUCAAUGGAUACGUGCAUGUUAUUUCAGAAUUAUGCAAAACGUCAAAAUCUGCUUCUGUGACCGCUGCUAUAGGCGUGGAGCUGAGGCUCGGCUUUUCCUUUUGUUCUGGGUGGAAGCAGCGGUGCCGCGGAGGGCCAGCCAGAUCCGGACCCUUCCCUUAGGGUCCAGUCUCCCCACACCCCAGCAGGGUGUCUUCUAGCCAUAAGGCCAAGGGAGUGGCAGAACUGGGCCGCCUCUCUGGUUGACAAGCAAACCACAUGCUAAGGCUUGGAGCAAGAGAGAAUUUGUGUCUAUUGGCAAAGAACUAAGCCAGGAAGACAUGGGCCAUCCCUCCGCUUUAGGGAAGCAUAUUUUAAACCUAAACGUUGAACUUCUUCUUUGGCCUCACCAGUGAAAACUUGUUGUCUUUAGUUCCUAAAGUUUCUUCUACUUUGGCACAUUCCCCAGUUGAGCAGCAGCCUCUAUGCUUCCACGUUCAGGAAAAAUUCCAGUCCUCAUAUCUUUUGUAGUUCACCCUCAAGCUCUCCCGCUUCACCAUCCAAUAGUUUCUCCCAAACCUUGGCACCCCCCUAGACUUUGCUUCCAAUGGUUUCUUCCAGACCACUUUUCCUAGAUGAAUAUAUUCGUUUACCUUACUAGGAAAAUUAUUGGAAGAUUUUUUCUUUUACUUGAAAUUGGAGGCAUUUUAAUAACUGGCGAACUGGAAUGUGUUUCUGUAUUUGUAGACAACCAUGAACCCAUGCAAGUAGGUGAACAUUCCACAGUGGCUGGGUGACCACAGCAGCUGCAUGCAGACAGGACUGCCCGUGCUUUGUGGGGAAUCAGAGAAUUUCCAAACUUGUUUCUCAGACUUCCGCAGAUCUCAUCACUUUGAUUUCUAAUCCAUGCUGUAUUGGUGAUUUUGUUUAUCGUUCCUGUAACUUGUUCUACAUUCCACAGUCUUUACCGUUUUAUGUUCAAAAUUACAACAAUCCCUGUCCAUUGAUUCCACUCUGGAACUCUUUGUUCAUGCCAAUUUUGAAAUUUUAAUACGAGCCUUCAAAUAAACACAGAAAAGAAAAAAAAAAAGGAAAAAAAAUAAAGUGUGUGCCUUGGGUGUUUUGAACCUGAUCUGCAUAAAACCAUAUUGUAUUCAAAUGCUGUAUCUUUCAUGAAAGGAUAAAUAUAUCUUCAAUGUAUUAAUGUAGCUGAUAAAAUAGUUAUAGUGCCUUGUUUUCUGAACUGAGAAGCCCAUAUCAAUGCACAACGUAAAGAAAGGACGGUUCGAGCUAUGAAAUGUUGAGGACACCUACACGUGAUUCUGGAGCCUUUCUCAUCAUAAGACUGUGGAAAAUACACAGUCGUUUAAGUUAAAAAUAAAAAGUAAAUUGAAA